AUGAACCUCUGAAAACUGCCGGCAUCUGAGGUUUCCUCCAAGGCCCUCUGAAGUGCAGCCCAUAAUGAAGGUCUUGGCGGCAGGUAAAUACACCCGCCCCGCGCCGGCUUCGCGUCCCCGCUGCGGGGCGCGGCGGCAACUUGGGGCGCUUGGCAGCGCGAGCCGGACGCCCACCCGCCGCAGACACACGAACACUUGGGGCGCCCGCGCAGCCACCGGAGGCGCUGGGUGGCGGCCCGGAGCGAGCGCGGGCACAUGGUCCCAAGCACCGCACGCCCCGCGGCAGGUUGGCGGCGAGGGAGGGGGCGCCGAGCCUUCCUCCUCCUCCUCUUCUUCCCCCUCUCCUUCUCCUCCUCCUCCUCCUCGCUCCGGACACUCGCUGGCUGCUCUUCCCUCUGCGCUUUCUCCCAGAUUCACUCUCCCUCUCUCUUUUUCUUUUCUUUCUUUCUUUCCGCUUUCUCCUUUCCAACCGCGGUCCCGGGCUGCUCCCAGGGAGGGGCGCGGGCGGCGAGCAGCUUGCAAACUCCGGCCUGGGACGGGAGCAGGUGCCGCCUCCAUCUGCUGGUGUCUGGAAGCGUGUGGUCUGCGCUAGGAGUUGUGCCCCUGCUGUUGGUUCUGCACUGGAAACAUGGGGCGGGGAGCCCCCUCCCCAUCACCCCUGUCAACGCCACCUGUGCCAUACGCCACCCAUGUCACAACAACCUCAUGAACCAGAUCAGGAGCCAACUGGCACAGCUCAAUGGCAGUGCCAAUGCCCUCUUUAUUCUCUAUUACACAGCCCAGGGGGAGCCGUUCCCCAACAACCUGGACAAGCUAUGUGGCCCCAACGUGACGGACUUCCCGCCCUUCCACGCCAACGGCACGGAGAAGGCCAAGCUGGUGGAGCUGUACCGCAUAGUCGUGUACCUUGGCACCUCCCUGGGCAACAUCACCCGGGACCAGAAGAUCCUCAACCCCAGUGCCCUCAGCCUCCACAGCAAGCUCAACGCCACCGCCGACAUCCUGCGAGGCCUCCUUAGCAACGUGCUGUGCCGCCUGUGCAGCAAGUACCACGUGGGCCAUGUGGACGUGACCUACGGCCCUGACACCUCGGGUAAGGAUGUCUUCCAGAAGAAGAAGCUGGGCUGUCAACUCCUGGGGAAGUAUAAGCAGAUCAUCGCCGUGUUGGCCCAGGCCUUCUAGCAGGAGGUCUUGAAGUGUGCUGUGAACCGAGGGAUCUCAGGAGUUGGGUCCAGAUGUGGGGGCCUGUCCAAGGGUGGCUGGGGCCCAGGGCAUCGCUAAACCCAAAUGGGGGCUGCUGGCAGACCCCGAGGGUGCCUGGCCAGUCCACUCCACUCUGGGCUGGGCUGUGAUGAAGCUGAGCAGAGUGGAAACUUCCAUAGGGAGGGAGCUAGAAGAAGGUGCCCCUUCCUCUGGGAGAUUGUGGACUGGGGAGCGUGGGCUGGACUUCUGCCUCUACUUGUCCCUUUGGCCCCUUGCUCACUUUGUGCAGUGAACAAACUACACAAGUCAUCUACAAGAGCCCUGACCACAGGGUGAGACAGCAGGGCCCAGGGGAGUGGACCAGCCCCCAGCAAAUUAUCACCAUCUGUGCCUUUGCUGCCCCUUAGGUUGGGACUUAGGUGGGCCAGAGGGGCUAGGAUCCCAAAGGACUCCUUGUCCCCUAGAAGUUUGAUGAGUGGAAGAUAGAGAGGGGCCUCUGGGAUGGAAGGCUGUCUUCUUUUGAGGAUGAUCAGAGAACUUGGGCAUAGGAACAAUCUGGCAGAAGUUUCCAGAAGGAGGUCACUUGGCAUUCAGGCUCUUGGGGAGGCAGAGAAGCCACCUUCAGGCCUGGGAAGGAAGACACUGGGAGGAGGAGAGGCCUGGAAAGCUUUGGUAGGUUCUUCGUUCUCUUCCCCGUGAUCUUCCCUGCAGCCUGGGAUGGCCAGGGUCUGAUGGCUGGACCUGCAGCAGGGGUUUGUGGAGGUGGGUAGGGCAGGGGCAGGUUGCUAAGUCAGGUGCAGAGGUUCUGAGGGACCCAGGCUCUUCCUCUGGGUAAAGGUCUGUAAGAAGGGGCUGGGGUAGCUCAGAGUAGCAGCUCACAUCUGAGGCCCUGGGAGGCCUUGUGAGGUCACACAGAGGUACUUGAGGGGGACUGGAGGCCGUCUCUGGUCCCCAGGGCAAGGGAACAGCAGAACUUAGGGUCAGGGUCUCAGGGAACCCUGAGCUCCAAGCGUGCUGUGCGUCUGACCUGGCAUGAUUUCUAUUUAUUAUGAUAUCCUAUUUAUAUUAACUUAUUGGUGCUUUCAGUGGCCAAGUUAAUUCCCCUUUCCCUGGUCCCUACUCAACAAAAUAUGAUGAUGGCUCCCGACACAAGCGCCAGGGCCAGGGCUUAGCAGGGCCUGGUCUGGAAGUCGACAAUGUUACAAGUGGAAUAAGCCUUACGGGUGAAGCUCAGAGAAGGGUCGGAUCUGAGAGAAUGGGGAGGCCUGAGUGGGAGUGGGGGGCCUUGCUCCACCCCCCCCCAUCCCCUACUGUGACUUGCUUUAGGGUGUCAGGGUCCAGGCUGCAGGGGCUGGGCCAAUUUGUGGAGAGGCCGGGUGCCUUUCUGUCUUGAUUCCAGGGGGCUGGUUCACACUGUUCUUGGGCGCCCCAGCAUUGUGUUGUGAGGCGCACUGUUCCUGGCAGAUAUUGUGCCCCCUGGAGCAGUGGGCAAGACAGUCCUUGUGGCCCACCCUGUCCUUGUUUCUGUGUCCCCAUGCUGCCUCUGAAAUAGCGCCCUGGAACAACCCUGCCCCUGCACCCAGCAUGCUCCGACACAGCAGGGAAGCUCCUCCUGUGGCCCGGACACCCAUAGACGGUGCGGGGGGCCUGGCUGGGCCAGACCCCAGGAAGGUGGGGUAGACUGGGGGGAUCAGCUGCCCAUUGCUCCCAAGAGGAGGAGAGGGAGGCUGCAGAUGCCUGGGACUCAGACCAGGAAGCUGUGGGCCCUCCUGCUCCACCCCCAUCCCACUCCCACCCAUGUCUGGGCUCCCAGGCAGGGAACCCGAUCUCUUCCUUUGUGCUGGGGCCAGGCGAGUGGAGAAACGCCCUCCAGUCUGAGAGCAGGGGAGGGAAGGAGGCAGCAGAGUUGGGGCAGCUGCUCAGAGCAGUGUUCUGGCUUCUUCUCAAACCCUGAGCGGGCUGCCGGCCUCCAAGUUCCUCCGACAAGAUGAUGGUACUAAUUAUGGUACUUUUCACUCACUUUGCACCUUUCCCUGUCGCUCUCUAAGCACUUUACCUGGAUGGCGCGUGGGCAGUGUGCAGGCAGGUCCUGAGGCCUGGGGUUGGGGUGGAGGGUGCGGCCCGGAGUUGUCCAUCUGUCCAUCCCAACAGCAAGACGAGGAUGUGGCUGUUGAGAUGUGGGCCACACUCACCCUUGUCCAGGAUGCAGGGACUGCCUUCUCCUUCCUGCUUCAUCCGGCUUAGCUUGGGGCUGGCUGCAUUCCCCCAGGAUGGGCUUCGAGAAAGACAAACUUGUCUGGAAACCAGAGUUGCUGAUUCCACCCGGGGGGCCCGGCUGACUCGCCCAUCACCUCAUCUCCCUGUGGACUUGGGAGCUCUGUGCCAGGCCCACCUUGCGGCCCUGGCUCUGAGUCGCUCUCCCACCCAGCCUGGACUUGGCCCCAUGGGACCCAUCCUCAGUGCUCCCUCCAGAUCCCGUCCGGCAGCUUGGCGUCCACCCUGCACAGCAUCACUGAAUCACAGAGCCUUUGCGUGAAACAGCUCUGCCAGGCCGGGAGCUGGGUUUCUCUUCCCUUUUUAUCUGCUGGUGUGGACCACACCUGGGCCUGGCCGGAGGAAGAGAGAGUUUACCAAGAGAGAUGUCUCCGGGCCCUUAUUUAUUAUUUAAACAUUUUUUUAAAAAGCACUGCUAGUUUACUUGUCUCUCCUCCCCAUCGUCCCCAUCGUCCUCCUUGUCCCUGACUUGGGGCACUUCCACCCUGACCCAGCCAGUCCAGCUCUGCCUUGCCGGCUCUCCAGAGUAGACAUAGUGUGUGGGGUUGGAGCUCUGGCACCCGGGGAGGUAGCAUUUCCCUGCAGAUGGUACAGAUGUUCCUGCCUUAGAGUCAUCUCUAGUUCCCCACCUCAAUCCCGGCAUCCAGCCUUCAGUCCCGCCCACGUGCUAGCUCCGUGGGCCCACCGUGCGGCCUUAGAGGUUUCCCUCCUUCCUUUCCACUGAAAAGCACAUGGCCUUGGGUGACAAAUUCCUCUUUGAUGAAUGUACCCUGUGGGGAUGUUUCAUACUGACAGAUUAUUUUUAUUUAUUCAAUGUCAUAUUUAAAAUAUUUAUUUUUUAUACCAAAUGAAUACUUUUUUUUUUAAGAAAAAAAAGAGAAAUGAAUAAAGAAUCUACUCUUG